GCUCAUCGUUUGUUGUUUAGAUAAUAUCAUGAACUGAUAAAUGCAGUUGCCACGUUGAUUCCCUAGGGCCUGGCUUACCGACUGAGGUCAUAAGAUAUUAUGCCUUCUCUUUAGACUUGGUCAGUGGAGAGGAAAUGGGCAAAGAACCAGCCUAUGGAGGUGACAAGGCCUUAGGGCCAAAAGUCUUGAGGGUGAAGGUUUAGGGCCUGCGCAGCUUCCCUGCCAUGCCCCGCAAGGUCUCGCAUUCGCAAGGCUUGUGACAGUGGGAGCCUCAUUACGGACUCUCCUAAAGUCCAUGGUGUCCUCUUUUCGCAUUUGCGCCCCGUGGGUGAUGCCCGAUGCCGCCCUUCCCAUCGCUCUCUUCCCCUUCAAGCGUAUCGCAACUGCAAAAACACCCAGCACAGACACUCCAUUUUCUAUCUUAAUGCAUUUAACUAGCACAACCUACAGGUUGUUCCAUCCCAGAGACUACCCUUUUCUCCAUAGACGUGACCAUCAACCAACCAGCGGUCAGAAUCAGUCAGCCUCUGUCAUGUUCCUAGGUCCUUGGCGAACUGGCUGGGCGGGGUCCCAGCAGCCUAGGAGUACAGUGGAGCAAUGCCUGACGUAAGUCAACAAAGAUCACGUGAGACGAAUCAGUCGCCUAGAUUGGCUACAACUAAGUGGUUGGGAGCGGGGAGGUCGCGGCGGCUGCGUGGGGUUCGCCCGUGACACAAUUACAACUUUGUGCUGGUGCUGGCAAAGUUUGUGAUUUUAAGAAAUUCUGCUGUGCUCUCCAGCACUGCGAGCUUCUGCCUUCCCUGUAGUUUCCCAGAUGUGAUCCAGGUAGCCGAGUUCCGCUGCCCGUGCUUCGGUAGCUUAAGUCUUUGCCUCAGCUUUUUUCCUUGCAGCCGCUGAGGAGGCGAUAAAAUUGGCGUCACAGUCUCAAGCAGCGAUUGAAGGCGUCUUUUCAACUACUCGAUUAAGGUUGGGUAUCGUCGUGGGACUUGGAAAUUUGUUGUUUCCAUGAAAUCCUGCGCAGUGUCGCUCACUACCGCCGCUGUUGCCUUCGGUGAUGAGGCAAAGAAAAUGGCGGAAGGAAAAGCGAGCCGCGAGAGUGAAGAGGAGUCUGUUAGCCUGACAGUCGAGGAAAGGGAGGCGCUUGGUGGCAUGGACAGCCGUCUCUUCGGGUUCGUGAGGCUUCAUGAAGAUGGCGCCAGAACGAAGACCCUACUAGGCAAGGCUGUUCGCUGCUACGAAUCUUUAAUCUUAAAAGCUGAAGGAAAAGUGGAGUCUGACUUCUUUUGCCAAUUAGGUCACUUCAACCUCUUGUUGGAAGAUUAUUCAAAAGCAUUAUCUGCAUAUCAGAGAUAUUACAGUUUACAGGCUGACUACUGGAAGAAUGCUGCGUUUUUAUAUGGCCUUGGUUUGGUCUACUUCUACUACAAUGCAUUUCAUUGGGCAAUUAAAGCAUUUCAAGAUGUCCUUUAUGUUGACCCCAGCUUUUGUCGAGCCAAGGAAAUUCAUUUACGACUUGGGCUCAUGUUCAAAGUGAACACAGACUACAAGUCUAGUUUAAAGCAUUUUCAGUUAGCCUUGAUUGACUGUAAUCCAUGUACUUUGUCCAAUGCUGAAAUUCAAUUUCAUAUUGCCCAUUUGUAUGAAACCCAGAGGAAGUAUCAUUCUGCAAAGGAGGCAUAUGAACAACUUUUGCAGACAGAAAACCUUCCUGCACAAGUAAAAGCAACUGUAUUGCAACAGUUAGGUUGGAUGCAUCAUAAUAUGGAUCUAGUAGGAGACAAAGCCACAAAGGAAAGCUAUGCUAUUCAGUAUCUCCAAAAGUCUUUGGAGGCAGAUCCUAAUUCUGGCCAAUCGUGGUAUUUUCUUGGAAGGUGUUAUUCAAGUAUUGGGAAAGUUCAGGAUGCCUUUAUAUCUUACAGGCAAUCUAUUGAUAAAUCAGAAGCAAGUGCAGAUACAUGGUGUUCAAUAGGUGUGUUGUAUCAGCAGCAAAAUCAGCCUAUGGAUGCUUUACAGGCAUAUAUUUGUGCUGUACAAUUGGACCAUGGGCAUGCCGCAGCCUGGAUGGACCUAGGUACUCUCUAUGAAUCCUGCAAUCAACCUCAAGAUGCCAUUAAAUGCUACCUAAAUGCAGCUAGAAGCAAACGUUGUAGUAAUACCUCUACGCUUGCUGCAAGAAUUAAAUUUCUACAGGCUCAGUUGUGUAACCUUCCACAAAGUAGUCUACAGAAUAAAACUAAAUUACUUCCUAGUAUUGAGGAGGCAUGGAGCCUACCAAUCCCCGCAGAGCUUACCUCCAGGCAGGGUGCCAUGAACACAGCACAGCAGGCUUAUAGAGCUCAUGAUCCAAAUACUGAACAUGUAUUAAACCACAGUCAAACACCAAUUUUACAGCAAUCCUUGUCACUACACAUGAUUACUUCUAGCCAAGUAGAAGGCCUGUCCAGUCCUGCCAAGAAGAAAAGAACAUCUAGUCCAACAAAGAAUGGUUCUGAUAACUGGAAUGGUGGCCAGAGUCUUUCACAUCAUCCAGUACAGCAAGUUUAUUCGUUGUGUUUGACACCACAGAAAUUACAGCACUUGGAACAACUGCGAGCAAAUAGAGAUAAUUUAAAUCCAGCACAGAAGCAUCAGCUGGAACAGUUAGAAAGUCAGUUUGUCUUAAUGCAGCAAAUGAGACACAAAGAAGUUGCUCAGGUACGAACUACUGGAAUUCAUAACGGGGCCAUAACUGAUUCAUCACUGCCUACAAACUCUGUCUCUAAUCGACAACCACAUGGUGCUCUGACCAGAGUAUCUAGCGUCUCUCAGCCUGGAGUUCGCCCUGCUUGUGUUGAAAAACUUUUGUCCAGUGGAGCUUUUUCUGCAGGCUGUAUUCCUUGUGGCACAUCAAAAAUUCUAGGAAGUACAGACACUAUCUUGCUAGGCAGUAAUUGUAUAGCAGGAAGUGAAAGUAAUGGAAAUGUGCCUUACCUGCAGCAAAAUACACACACUCUACCUCAUAAUCAUACAGACCUGAACAGCAGCACAGAAGAGCCAUGGAGAAAACAGCUAUCUAACUCCGCUCAGGGGCUUCAUAAAAGUCAGAGUUCAUGUUUGUCAGGACCUAAUGAAGAACAACCUCUGUUUUCCACUGGGUCAGCCCAGUAUCACCAGGCAACUAGCACUGGUAUUAAGAAGGCGAAUGAACAUCUCACUCUGCCUAGUAAUUCAGUACCACAGGGGGAUGCUGACAGUCACCUCUCCUGUCAUACUGCUACCUCAGGUGGACAACAAGGCAUUAUGUUUACCAAAGAGAGCAAGCCUUCAAAAAAUAGAUCCUUGGUGCCUGAAACAAGCAGGCAUACUGGAGACACAUCUAAUGGCUGUGCUGAUGUCAAGGGACUUUCUAAUCAUGUUCAUCAGUUGAUAGCAGAUGCUGUUUCCAGUCCUAACCAUGGAGAUUCACCAAAUUUAUUAAUUGCAGACAAUCCUCAGCUCUCUGCUUUGUUGAUUGGAAAAGCCAAUGGCAAUGUGGGUACUGGAACCUGUGACAAAGUGAAUAAUAUUCACCCAGCUGUUCAUACAAAGACUGAUCAUUCUGUUGCCUCUUCACCCUCUUCAGCCAUUUCCACAGCAACACCUUCUCCUAAAUCCACUGAGCAGAGAAGCAUAAACAGUGUUACCAGCCUUAACAGUCCUCACAGUGGAUUACACACAGUCAAUGGAGAGGGGCUGGGGAAGUCACAGAGCUCUACAAAAGUAGACCUGCCUUUAGCUAGCCACAGAUCUACUUCUCAGAUCUUACCAUCAAUGUCAGUGUCUAUAUGCCCCAGUUCAACAGAAGUUCUGAAAGCAUGCAGGAAUCCAGGUAAAAAUGGCUUGUCUAAUAGCUGCAUUUUGUUAGAUAAAUGUCCACCUCCAAGACCACCAACUUCACCAUACCCACCCUUGCCAAAGGACAAGUUGAAUCCACCCACACCUAGUAUUUACUUGGAAAAUAAACGUGAUGCUUUCUUUCCUCCAUUACAUCAAUUUUGUACAAAUCCAAAAAACCCUGUUACAGUAAUACGUGGCCUUGCUGGAGCUCUUAAAUUAGAUCUUGGACUUUUCUCUACCAAAACUUUGGUAGAAGCUAACAAUGAACAUAUGGUAGAAGUGAGGACACAGUUGCUGCAACCAGCAGAUGAAAACUGGGAUCCCACUGGAACAAAGAAAAUCUGGCGUUGUGAAAGCAAUAGAUCUCAUACUACAAUUGCCAAAUACGCACAAUACCAGGCUUCCUCCUUCCAGGAAUCAUUGAGAGAAGAAAAUGAGAAAAGAACACAACACAAAGAUCAUUCAGAUAACGAAUCCACAUCUUCAGAGAAUUCUGGAAGGAGAAGGAAAGGACCUUUUAAAACCAUAAAAUUUGGGACCAACAUUGACCUCUCUGAUAACAAAAAGUGGAAGUUGCAGUUACAUGAACUGACUAAACUUCCUGCUUUUGCGCGUGUGGUGUCAGCAGGAAAUCUUCUAACCCAUGUUGGGCAUACCAUUCUGGGCAUGAAUACAGUACAACUGUAUAUGAAAGUUCCAGGGAGUCGGACACCAGGUCACCAAGAAAAUAACAACUUCUGCUCUGUUAACAUAAAUAUUGGUCCAGGAGAUUGUGAAUGGUUUGUUGUACCUGAAGAUUAUUGGGGUGUUCUGAAUGACUUCUGUGAAAAAAAUAAUUUGAAUUUUUUAAUGAGUUCUUGGUGGCCCAACCUUGAAGAUCUUUAUGAAGCAAAUGUCCCUGUGUAUAGAUUUAUUCAGCGACCUGGAGAUUUGGUCUGGAUAAAUGCAGGCACUGUGCAUUGGGUUCAAGCUGUUGGCUGGUGCAAUAACAUUGCCUGGAAUGUUGGUCCACUUACAGCCUGCCAGUAUAAAUUGGCAGUGGAACGGUAUGAAUGGAACAAAUUGAAAAGUGUGAAGUCACCAGUACCCAUGGUGCAUCUUUCCUGGAAUAUGGCACGAAAUAUCAAAGUCUCAGAUCCAAAGCUUUUUGAAAUGAUUAAGUAUUGUCUUUUGAAAAUUCUGAAGCAAUAUCAGACAUUGAGAGAAGCUCUUGUUGCAGCAGGAAAAGAGGUUAUAUGGCAUGGGCGGACAAAUGAUGAACCAGCUCAUUACUGUAGCAUUUGUGAGGUGGAGGUUUUUAAUCUGCUUUUUGUCACUAAUGAAAGCAAUACUCAAAAAACCUACAUAGUACAUUGCCAUGAUUGUGCACGAAAAACAAGCAAAAGUUUGGAAAAUUUUGUGGUGCUCGAACAGUACAAAAUGGAGGACCUAAUCCAAGUUUAUGAUCAAUUUACACUAGUAAGUCAUUAACACGUGAGUACACUUAAUUAGGUGGGUUUAAAGCAAUGGUCUUUGACUUUGCUAACUGAUAAAAAUGUGUUAAGAAGAAACUUAAAUUUUCCAUUGGUGCAGUAUAUACUUUGUAAGGAAAAAUAUUAGUAGCCAUCCUCGUAUUUCACGUUAGUUUUUCUAUAUGAAACUGUUUAUUACCAUUUUUGCUUCUCAGUGAGAAUGCCCCCAAAGAAUAGUUACACUAAUUACAUUUGUAAAUGUCUGUAUGUUUUUAGAAUAUUUUUUAGUUUUUAUGUUACUUACAUAACUUAUAAAACCUUUGUACAUGUAGGUUACUUAAUUCUUCUGUAGUAAUUAUCUGAAAGAAAUGUGUGGGUUUUUUUCAUGUACUUUGUGGUUUAAAGAUUCCAGAAGAGUUUGCCUGAUAGCACUACUUGAUGGAGCUUGCUUGACUAGAUUAUAUGAUAUAUAAGCCUCAUGAAAAAUAUGUUCAGUGUCAUCUAGCUGUGGCAUUUUCAUAAGCCAAUUGCUAGUGAAAUUUUAAUUUACUUUAAAAUUAUUUUUCCACACAACUUUUCUUUUAGCAAUCUAAAAAAUUGGUUAACUUUUAACAGUAUUCCAAACGUUGUUCACUAAAUGAUGAAAAAUGGAGGUAAUAGCGCCGCACUCUUAACUGAUUCUAAUGAAGAAAGUAAGAGCAUCUCAACUGAGCACAGUGUCUCAUGCCUGUAAUCCCAGCACUUUGGGAGUCCAAGGCGGGCAGAUCACCUGAGGUCAGGAGUUCAAGACCAGCCUAACCAACAUGGAGAAACCCCAUCUCUACUAAAAAUACAAAAUUGGCCAUGCAAGGUGGUGGAUGUUUAUAAUCCCAGCUACUCGGAGGCUGAGGCACGAGAAUUGCUUGAAUCCAAGAGGCAGGGGUUGCGGUGAGCCGAGAUCGCGCCAUUGCACUCCAGUCUGGGCAACAAGAGCAAAACUCUGUCUCAAAAAGAAAAAAAAGAAAAGAGCAUCUCUCUUAGGAAACUGUUGAGAUUUCAUGUAUCUUGUAAACUCACUUCAUAAAAAGGCUGUCUUUUAUAGUCAUAAGCUAGCAAACACUAUUAAGGAUUUAUAUAACAAAAUCUUAACUUUUAUUUCUAGGCUCUUUCAUUAUCAUCCUCAUCUUGAUAUAGUUCCAUGAAUAUUAAAUGAGAUUAUUUCUGCUCUUCAGGAAAUUUCUGCACCACUGGUUUUGUAGCUGUUUCAUAAAACUGUUGACUAAAAGCUAUGUCUAUGCAACCUUCCAAGAAUAGUAUGUCAAGCAACUGGACACAGUGCUGCCUCUGCUUCAGGACUUAACAUGCUGAUCCAGCUGUACUUCAGAAAAAUAAUAUUAAUCAUAUGUUUUGUGUACGUAUGACAAACUGUCAAAGUGACACAGAAUACUGAUUUGAAGAUAGCCUUUUUUAUGUUUCUCUAUUUCUGGGCUGAUGAAUUAAUAUUCAUUUGUAUUUUAACCCUGCAGAAUUUUCCUUAGUUAAAAACACUUUCCUAGCUGGUCAUUUCUUCAUAAGAUAGCAAAUUUAAAUCUCUCCUCGAUCAGCUUUUAAAAAAUGUGUACUAUUAUCUGAGGAAGUUUUUUACUGCUUUAUGUUUUUGUGUGUUUUGAGGCCAUGAUGAUUACAUUUGUGGUUCCAAAAUAAUUUUUUUAAAUAUUAAUAGCCCAUAUACAAAGAUAAUGGAUUGCACAUAGACAAAGAAAUAAACUUCAGAUUUGUGAUUUUUGUUUCUAAACUUGAUACAGAUUUACACUAUUUAUAAAUACGUAUUUAUUGCCUGAAAAUAUUUGUGAAUGGAAUGUUGUUUUUUUCCAGACGUAACUGCCAUUAAAUACUAAGGAGUUCUGUAGUUUUAAACACUACUCCUAUUACAUUUUAUAUGUGUAGAUAAAACUGCUUAGUAUUAUACAGAAAUUUUUAUUAAAAUUGUUAAAUGUUUAAAGGGUUUCCCAAUGUUUGAGUUUAAAAAAGACUUUCUGAAAAAAUCCACUUUUUGUUCAUUUUCAAACCUAAUGAUUAUAUGUAUUUUAUAUGUGUGUGUAUGUGUACACACAUGUAUAAUAUAUACAGAAACCUCGAUAUAUAAUUGUAUAGAUUUUAAAAGUUUUAUUUUUUACAUCUAUGGUAGUUUUUGAGGUGCCUAUUAUAAAGUAUUACGGAAGUUUGCUGUUUUUAAAGUAAAUGUCUUUUAGUGUGAUUUAUUAAGUUGUAGUCACCAUAGUGAUAGCCCAUAAAUAAUUGCUGGAAAAUUGUAUUUUAUAACAGUAGAAAACAUAUAGUCAGUGAAGUAAAUAUUUUAAAGGAAACAUUAUAUAGAUUUGAUAAAUGUUGUUUAUAAUUAAGAGUUUCUUAUGGAAAAGAGAUUCAGAAUGAUAACCUCUUUUAGAGAACAAAUAAGUGACUUAUUUUUUUAAAGCUAGAUGACUUUGAAAUGCUAUACUGUCCUGCUUGUACAACAUGGUUUGGGGUGAAGGGGAGGAAAGUAUUAAAAAAUCUAUAUCGCUAGUAAAUUGUAAUAAGUUCUAUUAAAACUUGUAUUUCAUAUGAAAAAUUUGCUAAUUUAAUAUUAACUCAUUUGAUAAUAAUACUUGUCUUUUCUACCUCUCCUUUCUGAAGCAUUUUUAUUUAAUCACAUUCUUCUUUGUAACAGCUUUCCAGAGAACUUUAGUGAAGAAUCAUAGAAUGCUUUAAUAGAAGCUAUUUAAAUAUCAAAAGGGAAGUUAUAGUCUUAUCAGGUGAAAUGUCUUGAUCAUUGCAUUAUUGCAGUACUUUCUUCAGACAAGUUUGGAAUAUUUUGGCUUCCUAGAAAUAGUUGUUAGAAAACUCAUGAAGAUAUUUUAUUAAGUUAGGUAGUUGAAAUCUGUUAGCAGUAAUCAUCACAUACCUAAUUUCAGAAAAAAAAAUGCAAUUUGUAAUUAAGGAAGAAAAAUCAUAAGUACUUCUAGAUAUUUUAAAUGCUGAUAUUUUUGUAAUUUUCUUGUAAAUUUUCUUGUUCAGAAAUCAUUGAGAUUAAAAUUCAGGACUUUUUUUUACCCCUCUCAAACAAAAACUACAGAUCAACCAUCAGGAAACAUCUAGAAUACCAGAGCUAUACCUGAACUUUUCUUAACCGGUUGUUUUGUAUUACUAACGUAACAUCUUAUGUCUUAACUCUUUAAGAUGAUUUAUGGCUAGGAUUACUAUAUGUUGAAUUUACAGAAUUGACCUAGUCAUGAAAAUGACUUUACCUGUUUAUCUUUUACACUUCUUUUGUUAUUGUUGUUUGUUUUUGUUUUUGUUUUUUGAGAUGGAAUCUCAGUCUGUCACCCAGGCUGGAGUGCAGUGGAGUGAUCUUGGCUCACUGCAACCUCUGCCUCCUGGGUUCAAGCUCCUGGGUUCAAGCUCUUCUGUCACAGCCUCCCGAGUAGCUGGGACUACAGGUGUGCAUCACCACACCCAGCUAAUUUUUUUUGUAUUUUUAGUAGAAACAAGGUUUCACCAUAUUAGCCAGGCUGGUCUCGAACUCCUGUCCUCAUGAUCCACCUUCCUCAGUCUCCCCAAAUGCUGAGAUUACAGGCAUGAGCCACUGCACCUAGCCCUUUUACAUGUUUUCUAAUGCAUAUUUGGAUUAUCCAUUGAGAGUAAUACUUUUCAGAAGCUUACACUCUUUAAAUAGGCAGAAAACCAAAACUGAAAAUCAAAUAUAUCACUAGUUUGGAAUUAAUCUAGAUAAAUGAAGUUCUGUUAUCUACUGUAAUCAAUUUAUCACCUUUGUAAGUUGCAUUUUGGAGAUUUAAAAAAAAAAGAUUCUUUUUGUUGUCCUUUUUACUGCUGGAGGUGUGAAGUUGCUCAAGCUGACCCUACCUACAUGCCUUUCAAUAAAAGAAAUUUAUAGCACACACAUUGUUCAGAAAAUAAUCCAGUAGUUGCAUAAAACAGAUACUUUUCCCAAAAGAAAACAAGAACUAUGUGGAAAACAGCCAUAUCCUUUUUCUCAGCAAUUAAACAUGAAGUUUUCUUAGAUUGAUUUGCAUUUCUGCCAUGUAUAUAUAAUGUGGCUUGCUUAAUCUGGUUGUUACCAGAAAUCUCGGCUUCUGCUUUUUUUUUUUUUUUUUUUUUUUUUUUCCUGAGACAGAGUUUUACUCUUGUUGCCUAGGCUGGAGUGCAGUGGCACAGUCUCGGCUUACUGCAACCACUGCCUCUUGGGUUCAAGCGAUUCUCCUGCCUCAGCCUCCCGAGUAGCUGGGAUUACAGGCCACCCCACUGGGCUAAUUUUUUGUAUUUUUUAGUAGAGAAGGGGUUUUGCCAUGUUAGGCAGGCUGGUCUCAAACUCAUGACCUCAGGUUGACCCGUGUCAACCUCCCAAAGUGCUAGGAUUAUAGGUGUGAGCCACUGCACCCAGCAUGCUUCUGUAUUUUAAUAUAAACCUUGGCUGCUUUUCCAAAGUAAUAAAUUGCAAACUAGGAUGUUCAAGAUACUAGUAUAUAUCAACUUAAGAUUGUGAUUACAUAAUUUUAGUGUAAAGAGUCUAUUCCUCCUAAAUAUUUGAGCCUUUUUGUUAGCCAUUAAGUUACUAUGACAUAUUUUUAUUUAAGACAUGUUCUAAUUAGCUUCUCCUAAUAGACAAAUAUGGAAAAGAUGUGAACUUGUCCUCUACACUCCAUAUGCACAAGGCUUUUACCAUCUAAUAUGGGACAUACAUGGAAAUAAAUAACAAAAAGAGUACUAUUACAGUUUGUGUUCAAGAGUUGUCUGGACACUGUGGCUCACACCUGUAACCCCAGCAUUUUGGGAGGCUGAGGCAGGCCGAAGUCACCUGUGGUCAGGAGUUUGAGACCAGCCUGGCCAACAUAGCGAAAUCCCUUCUCAUAAAAGUACAAAAAUUAGCCAGGCAUGGUGGCGCAUGCCUGUACUGCCAGCUUCUUGGGAGGCUGAGGCAGGAAAAUCACUUGAACCUGGGAGGCAGAGCUUGCAGUGAGCUGAGACCGUACCACUGCACUCCAGCCUGGGUGACAGAGGGAGACUCCAUCUCAAAAAAAAGAAAAGUAUUAAGUCAUCUACAUUCACACUUCAUAACAUGAAUGUUUGGGGACCUCACGUUCUUUGUCAUAACUAAGACAUUAGCUGCGUAAACAGGUAACUGGAGAAGGGAUCUGAUGGUGCAAAACUCCUCAGUCAUGUUAAGACUUUCUGACUGUUCUUGUAGUUAGUAACAGAGCUAUUGACUGGUUUUAUAUAAAAGAAUCAAUAAGUUUGCAAAAUCUUUCUUCUGUCACACUCCCAUUUGUUUCAAUGCUGCAUUUGUUCUUUACACAUAUCCCAGGGGAAUAUAUCUAAGACUAAAAGUCCAGGGAAGAAAUGCUUAGUACUUGGAAUUUUCAUUUUGUGGAAUGGAAGUAAAGGCACAAAUUUUGGAAACAUUUUAAGGAAUAAAGUUCACAGAUCCCAUUAUCUUCCUGGUGGAGAAGUGUCCUUCUAACAAGACACAAUCCAGAAAGGACAGAGCAGAAGAUUAUAGUGACAUCUAAGUGAUGUUAAUUGAUUUAGAAAGGAACAGAUGGAUAUGUGAAUCUCAAAUUUAGAAAUGCAAGUUAGUGAAUCUACAAGUGAGGAGAGUACAAGUCCACCUUGUGGCAUCACAUAAAGGGGAGGGAAAACGAGCUAAAAGAUCAGGAAGAGUAAAUAUUUUGAAAACCAUGUCUAUAUUAUUCUGAAAAGAUAGAAAAAGAGAUCUCUUCGGGUUAGUGCAAGGUUGCUGUGAUGUUAACCUGAGCAGCUUCAGUGAAAUAAGGUACUUAUACCUAGAACUCAAAGAUAUUUCCCUGUGGAUUAAUUUUUUAGAUUUUACGUUUAUAUUCAUAAUCCAUUUUGAGUUAAUUUUUUCUAUAAAUCGUAAGGCAUACAGCAAUAUUGUUUUGUUUUUACAUUUUGUGUCUAAGCUCCAGGACCAUUUGUUUCUAACUCAAAGGUAUCAGUAGAGUGAAUUUGUGUUGGUUGAUUUUUGUGUUUUCUAGACUGUUUCAUUUUUAUAUCUGUUCAUCUUUGUGCCAGUGCUUCACUAUCUUCAUUACUGUGGUUAUAUAAUAGGUCUUAAUAUUGGACAAAGCAAUUCUUUAUUCUUUUUAAAUAUUGUUUUACCUAUUGUAGAGUCUUUGCCUUUCUAUAUAAAUUUUAGAAUAAGCUUGUCUAGGGCUACAGAAAACCUUAUUAUGAUUUUGAUAUGUUGUGCUAACUAUAUAAACAACAGUGUUCUAAUAUCUAGAAUACAUAUCUACAUAAAUAUGCUUGCAAUGUAAGUAACAGGUUAAUAAAAUUAAGAAAAUUGGCAUCUUUAAUAUGUUGAGUAUCCCAGUCCAUAUGGUGUUUCUCUCUAUUUAAGUCCUUGUUGGUUUUUUUCAUUAGCUUUUAUAAUGAUCAGUAUGCAGAUCCUUUACAGAUCUUAUACCUACAGAUUAUUUUAUUUUUUAAGUUGAUAAUAUUUCCCAUAUAUAUGGGGGUACAUGUGAUAUGUUGUUACAUAUAUAGAAUGUGUAAUUAUUAAAUCGGAAUAUUUUGAGUGUCCAUUACUUUCAGGACUUACCUUAUCUAUGAGUUGGGGAAAAUUCAAGUCCUUUUCUAUUUCUCCCUUGAAAUAUACAUUGUUAUUAACUACAGUCAUUCAUCUAUACUGCUGUUGAAUGAUAAAACAUAAUACAUUUUAUCUAACUGUAUGUUUGUACCCAUUAACCUACUUGUCUUUAUCAGCUCCCUCCCAGCCAUCUAUCCUUCUCAGCCUCUGGUAACUAUCAUUCUACUCUCUACCUUUACAAAAUCUUUUUUUUAGCCCCCACAUAUGAAUGAGAGCACGCAAUGUUUACCUUUCCACAGUUAGGUUGUUUCACUUAACAUAAUAUACUUGGGCCAGGCUCAGUGGCUCAUACCUGUAAUCCCAGCAGUUUGGGAGCCAAGACAGGUGGAUUACUUGAGCCCAGGAAUUUGAGAUCAUCCUGGGUAACCUGGUGAAAUUCCACCUCUGCAAAAAAUACACAAAUUAGCUGGGUGUAAUGGCGUGUGUCUGUAUUGCCACCUACCCGGGAGGCGGAAGUUGAAGGAUCUCUUGAGCCUGGAAGGUCAAGGAUGCAGUGAUCCUUGAUUGUGCCACUGCCGCUAGCCUGGGAGACAGGGCAAGAUUCUGUCUCGAAAAAAGUAAACUAAUGAACUCCACUUCCAUUCAUUUUCUCCAAAUGACAUUAUUUAAUUUUUGUGAUUUUUUUUUAAUCUCAUUAUGGUUUUGAUUUGAAUAUCCUCAUGCUUAGACAUGUUGAGCAGUUUUAAAUGCCUUUUGGCAGUCUGUAUGUCUUUGAGAAUUAUCCAUUCAUGUAAUUUGCCUACCUUCUAAUGGGAUUGUUUUUAUAAAUGAGUUGUAUGAGCUUGUAUUUUCUGGAUAUUAUUUGUCUCUUGUCAGACGAAUGGUUUGCAAAUAUUUUUUCCCCUUCUGUGGGUUGUCUGUUCACUCCAGUGAUUGUUUCCUUAGCUGUGCAGAAGCUUUUUAGUUUAAUAUAGUACCAUUUGUUUAUUUUUGUUUUUGUUGGCUGUGCUUUUGAGCUCUUAGCCAUAAAAUCUUAGCCUAGGUCAGUGUUCUGUAGUGUUUUCCCUGUGUUUCUUCUAGUAGUAGUAUACUUUUAGGUCUUUAAGUCUGAUCCAUCUGGAGGUUAUUUUACCUUAUUUUAUUAUUUUAUUUUAUUUUAUUUAUUUUUUAUAUUUUUUAUUUUAUUUUAUUUUGUAUUUUUUGAGAUGGAGUCUUGCUCCAGUCACCCAGGCUGGAGUACAGUGGCACGAUCGUGGCUCACUGCAAUCUCCACCUCCUGGGUUCAAGCAGUUCUCCUUCCUCUGCUUCCCAUGCUGCUGGAACUACUGGCAUCUACCACCACACCUGGCUAAUUUUUGUAUUUUUAGUAGAGACGGGGUUUCAUCAUGUUGGCCAAGCUGGUCUCGAACUGCUGUUCAAGUGAUCUUCUCACCUCAGCCUUCCAGAGUGCUAGGAUUGCACUCUGUGCCCAGCCUGGAAGUGAUUUUUUUAAUUCAUUAAGUAAAGGGAUCGAGUUUCAUUCUAUUGCAUUUGGACCUACAAUUUCUCCCACCACUGUUUACUAAAGAUAGUGUCCUUUUUCAAAUGUAUUUUCAUCUUUGUUUAAAAAAAAGUCACUUGGCCAUAAAUAUCUGGAUUUAUUCUUGGGUUAUCCAAUUUGCUUCCAGUGAUCUAUGUGUCUUUUUAUAUCAAUAGUAUGCUCUUUUGGCUAUUGUAGCCUGUAAUAUAUUUUUAUGUCAGGUAGUAUGAUGUCUCUUUUUGCUGUGGAUUGCUUUGGCUAUUCAGCCAGUUUUGUUACUAGUUCCACAUGAAUUUUAGGAUUGUUUUAUCUAUGUCUGUGAAAAAUGACAUUGAUAUUUCAGUGGGGAUUGGAUUGAAUCUAUAGAUUGCUUUGAGCAGAAUGUUCAAUUUAUUGACAUUAAUUCCUUGGAUCCGUGAGCAUGGGAUGCAAUUCGAUGCAAUUUAUCAGGGAUAAUAGUGUGUAGUUUUCUUUUUUGUUGUGUGUUUUCUGGUUUGGGGCGGUAUGUUCAAUUUAAGGACAUUAAUUCCUCUGAGCCAAGAGCAGGGGAUACAUUUUUCAAGGUUAAUGGUAUAUAGAUUUUUGUUGUGUGUUUUCUGGUUUUGGUAUCAGAUAAAGCUGGUCUUAUAGAAUGCGUUAAGUGUAAUUCCUUCCUACUCAGUGUUUUGAAAUAGGAAGAUUGCUGUUAAUUCUUUGUUACAUAAUUGGUAGAAUUCAGCAGUGAAUCCAUUUAGUCUUGGGCUUUUCUUUGUUGAGAUACUUGUGAAUAUUGAAUGAAUAUCACUACUUUUUAUUCUUCAGCGUUUUUUUAUUUAUUCUUGAUUGUUUUUUGUUUUUGUUUUUGUUUUUGUUUUGACAUGGAAUCUCACUCUGUCACCCAGGCUGGAGUACAGUGUCACGAUCUCAGCUCACUGCAACCUCCGCCUCGCAGGUUCAAGCAGUUCCCUUCCUCUGUCUCCCUAGUAGCUGGGUUACAGAUGCCCAGCUAAUUUUUGUGUGUUUAGUAGAAACAGGGUUUCACCGUCUUGGCCAGGCUGAUCUUGAACUCCUGACCUCAUGAUCCACCUGCCUCAGCCUCCCAAAGUACUGGGAUUUACAAGCAUGAGUCACCAUGCCCCGCUAUUCUUGAUUCAUCCUAGCUAGUUUAUAUGUUUCCAGAAAUCCAUCCAUUACUUCUAAGUUUUUGCAAUUAGUUUAUACUUGUUCAUAAUAAUGUCUCAUGAUCUUUUCUAUUUCUCUAGUAUCAGAUGUAAUGUUUCCUUUUUUACUUCUAAUUUUAUUUGGUCUUCUUGCUUCUUUCCUUGGUUAGCUUAGCUAGUGGUUUAUCAGUUUUGUCUUUUCAAGAACGAACUUUGUGUUGAUUGAUCCUUUGUAUUCUUUUUUAGUCUCUUUUUCUGUUAGUUUUGCUGUCACCUUUAUUUCUUUUCUUCUGCUAUUUUUGGGUUGGUUGAUUCUUGUUUUUCUAAUAAGUGCAUCAUUCGAUUGCAUAGUUGAGAUCUUUGUACUAUUUUGAUGUAAGCACUUAUUGUUACACAUUUCUCUUUUUUACUUGCCUUUGUUAUAUAUAUAUAUUUUGGUGUGUUGUUUCCAUUUUCAUUCAUUUAAAUUUUUUUCAUUUUAAUCUUUAUUUCUUCAUUGACCAGUGGUUGUUGUUAAAGAGAAUGUUAUUUAAUUGCCAUGUAUGUAUAGUUUCCACAGUUCCUAUUGCUAUUAAUUUCUAGUUUUUUGUGGGGGUUUUCUUGUUGCUAUUGUGUGGUUUUAUGGUUUUUUGUUUUCAGUUUUUUAAAUUGAGUUAGCGUCUCACUUAUGAGGCUGGUCUUGAACUCCUGGGCUCAAGCGAUUAUCUCACUUCAGCUUCCCAAAGUGCCAGCUUUACAGAUGUGACCCACCAUGCCCAGCCUUUUUAAUUUUUUAAUGUUAAUUUUUUUUUUUUUUUUUGAGACAGUGUCUUGCUCUGGACUGCAGUGGGUUAUUCAUGGCUCACUGCAGCCUUGACCACUGGUCUCAAGCAAUCCUCCCACCUCAGCUCCCUGAGCAGCUGUGACUAUAGGCACAAGUCACCAUGCCCAGCUGAUUUAAAUUUUUAAUAGAGACAAGGUCUAGCUAUGUUGCUCAUACUGGUCUCGAACUCCGGAGCUUACACAGUCCUCCUGCCUUGGACUCCCAAAGUAUUGAGAUUACAGGCAUGAGCCACUGAGCUCAAUCUUAAUUUCUUGUUCUAUUCCACUGUGGUCCUAGAAUAUACUUGAUGUGAUUUUGGCUCUCUAAAAUUUUUUCAGAAGUGUUUUGUGGCUCAGCAUGGUCUGUCCUAGAGGAUCUUUCAUGUGCUGAUGAGAAAAGAGUAUGCUCUCUGCAAUUUUGGGGUAAACCAUUCUGUAGGUUUCUGUUAGGUACUUUUAGUCCAAUGUCUGUUCUUAAGUCCAGUGUUUUAUUGUUGAUUUUCUGUCUGGAUGACUGGUCUAAUGCAAGUGGGGAUUGAAGUUGCCCACUGUUCUUGCAUUGAAAUAUCUCUCCUUAGAUCAAUUAAUAUUUGCUUUAUGAACCUGGGUGUUCCAGUACUGGUUGCAUGUAUAUGGAACUGUUAUUUCUUCUUGCUGGAUUGAUUCCUUUAUCAUUAUAUAAUGUAUGUAAUGACCUUCUUUGUCUUUUUUUUUUUUUACCUGCCUGUGGCUUAAAGUAUGGCUACUCCUGCUUACUUCUGGCUUGCAUAUGCUAUUUUCCCUCCGUUACUUUCAGUCUGUGUGCUGACUUUUCAGGUAUAGUGAGUUUCCUGUAGAGAGCAUAUAAGUGGAUGAUAUUUUUUAAUCCAUAGAGUCUAUAUAUUUUAUAAAGUGUGGAAUUUAGUCCACUUAUAUUUAAGGUUAUUGAUAUGUUGGUAUGUGAGGUUCUGUACCUGUCAUACUGUUGUUUUUUGAUUUUGUGUAUUCCUAUUUCUUUCCUUUUCUCUUAUUGCUAUUGUGAUUUGGCAGUUAUCUGUAGUGGUACCAUUUGAGUCCUUUCCUAUUUGUAUGUUUUCUUAUAAUUGAGUUUUAUACCUUGAUGUGUUUUUAUGAUGACAAAUAUUGUUCUUUCAUUUUCAGAUUUAGAACUCCCUUGAGCAAUUCUGGUAGGAUUCAUCUAGUGGUGAUGAAUUCCCUCAGUGUUUGCUUAUCUGGGGAAGACUUUAUUUCUCCUGCAUUUAUGAAGGAAAAUUGAACUGGAUAUAGCAUUCUGGGCUGACAGGUGUUUUCUUUCAUUACUUUGGUUAUAUCGUCUUAUUCUAACCUUUCCUGCAAGGUUUCUGCUGAGCAGUCUGUUCGUCUACUGGGAUUUCUUUUAUUGAUAACGAGACACUUUUCUCUUGAUGUUCUUAGAAUUUUCUCUUUGUAAUUGACUUUAGACAGUUUCACUAUAAUGUGCCAUGGAGAAGAUUUUUUUUGUGUCGCAUCUGAGGGGAUCGUGGGAUCUCCUGUAUCUGGAUAUGUAAAUCUCUUGCUAGACUUGGGAAGUUUCAUUUAUUAUUUUGCUAAACAGGUUGUGAACCUUUUGUUAUCUUUUCAUAUGCCGAGAUACCAGUAAUUUAUUUAUUUGGUCACUUUGUGGUGUCCUAUAUAUUGUAAAGAUUUUGUAAUUCUUUUUCAUUCUUUUAAAAAUGUUUGCCUGGUUUGCUGAUUCCAAAAGACUUGUUUUCAAGUUCUGAGGUUUUUUUUUCUUCUGUUUGAUCUAGCCAAUUCUUGCUGCUUCCAAACCUAGUGUGUACUUCAUUCAAAGAAUUCUUCAGUUCCAGAAUUGAUUUAGUUCUUUUUAAUGACGUGUCUUUUUGGUAUACUUCUCAUUCAUGAACUGACUUGUUUUUGAUUUUGAUUUUUUAAACAUGUGUUUUAAAAUGUUCUUCUUUCUGAGCUUCUUUACAAUUACUACCGUCUUGUUCUGCCGUUUUGUGUAUAUAUUUUUUAUUUGGAUCUAUUCCUGGAGAAUUAUUAUGUCCUUUGGAAAUGUCAUAUUAACUUGCUUUCUCAUGUGUCUUUUCAUUGAUAUCUGCAUAACUGGUGUAUCAAUCACUUCCAAUUUUCUUAAUUCCCUUUCAUAGAGAAGGACAUAUUUCUGAGGAUGAAUCUGUGGCAUUGGUUGGGUAAGGCACUUUGGCUUUGAUUCUGGGUUCAUGCAGUAGGAUAGUCUCUGUAUGAUUUCUUUGAUUGUAAAGAGCAUCAGUGGUAUCUGAGACUUUUUCACUGGCUCUGCGGGUGCAGUUAGUAUUGGAGGCUGUAGUGCAGUUUUACCUGGGACUGGGAUGCCAGACUGGCCCAUCUUUAGGCCCUAGUGGUGGCAGCAGUGCACUCAACAAUUGUCUCUUUGGGCUUCAGUGUGACCUGCAGUGGCACCAGUGUUAGUGUGUCCAAGGAGGCCAGUGCUUGGGCCCCCAGGUGACUUAUUCUGAUGCUGAUAGUGGCAGCUGUGAGCUUGGCAUGUAGGUAGGUUCUUGGGCCUCUGGACACCUGAUGUGGCAUGGAUGAUGGCGCUGGCAGUGACAGUGGAAGGAUGCCUCAAGCAGUGUGUAUCAGGCUGCAGUGAGCUCAUGAGGCCAGUCUCCAGGCCUACAUCUGAUACACACAUAUAGGUAUCAGCUGUGGUUAUAGCAACCAGGUGGAUAAGACCCAGCCUGAGUCCCCCACAAGGAGUGUUCAGGGGUCAACAUUGGUGGACUGAGCUGGGUCACACCCAAGAUCCAGACUUUCCUCGGGCAUAGGUAGGGGAUUAAACCUGCUCAGGCUGGGUUUUCCUGAGGACUGAUAGUGUGUACAUGUGCUGGGCCUGGAAAGCAGGGGUUAGAGGGAUUCUCAGGCCACUGGCAGAAUGCUUAGGUGAAUGGUGGCAGCAUUCAUGCCAUUGCCCUGCCACUAGGCAGGCAAUACUGGUUUCAGUGAUAGCAGCUUUGGCUCACAUGUUGGGAGCACAUGUGCUACUCAUGCCUCAGCUCUGGUAGUGCUCACAACUACGUCUUGGGGACAGCAGCCGUCUUUUCUGUUGCACCUCAGCCCCAGCACUGCUGGGCUCCAGAACAGUAGGGAGUCUGUUGGGGGCAUGGCUCUAGAAUGGCACUUUCUUUGCAUCUCGGACAUACCUUUGUCCCAGGUAGCCCAUGGUUGGUUAUACCUAAAUUCCAGAGUCAGCAGCACAUGCAUUCCUUGCACCUCAGCCCUGAUUCCUGUGGGCUUCAAAGAUGGUCCCUGGUCUGUUUGGGAUGAUGUUCCAAAGAGUGUGCCUUGCUGUAACUGCUUAGGUCUCAAGGAAUGUGAGGGAUGCUGCACAGGCUAUAUGCUUAAAGGCAGUACCAUCCUACUAUCUCUCUGCAGCUCCCUAUGUUAGUUUCAGGGCCCACUGAGUGGGGUUAGCUCUCCAGUGGCUAGAAUUACAGAGAUACCUGGUAUGAACAUGGAUCCCUGGAGAUCACUGACCCCUGACCUUGUUGGAAAGUCUCUCAGCACCCAGCCCAUCCUGGCCAAGCAGGCUGCCUCACCUAAUUCUUGUUUGCUUUAGGUAUCACCUCUUUUCCAGUGCUCUCUCUUGGAUGAUCUAGUUCAUGCAUGAUUACUCACUUUGGUUCUCUUAUUGGAGAAAGCAAAUGCCCCUAGUCGGCCAUCAUGAAGGCUUCUUCAUUUCUUUUUGAGAGAUGUAAGUGGUAUUGGGUUUUUAAUUUCCAUCUCCACAUGUUCAUCUUUAGUCUACAGAAUGAUGAUUGACUUUUUUCUGUUUAUUUAAUAUCCUCUGAUCAUGCAGAACUCAUUCAUUAGUUCAAAAAAGAUUUUUGUAAAUUGUUUUACAUUUUCCAUGUGUACAGUCUGCAAGAAAGAAGUGUUAUUUCCUCCCUUUCUAUAUGUUGUUCAUGUGUUUAUUUUUCUUACUUUAUCACAGCAGUUGGAAUUUCCAGUAUUGUGUUAAAUAAGAAUGAUGAAAAUGGACACUCUUGCUUUCUAUUGUAUCCAAUCUUUUUUUUAAAAAAAUUUCUUAGCAGUAUGAUAUUAGCUGUAGUUUUAUAAGGAAAUGCUCUUUAUUAAGAAUAUCCUAUUCUUAGUUUCCUAGCAGGUUUUACCAUUGAGUGUUGAAACUUUCAAGUGCUCUCAUUUUUCUGCAUCUGUUGAUAACAACCAUAUGACUUUUCUUUUUAUUAGAUUACAUUAACUGAUUUUCAAUGUUGAAGUAGCUUUACGUAGAUGAACCUUAUCCCAACUGUUUGUGUUGCAUGCGUAUUUAAUUUUGUAUUUGCUGAGCUUAGCUUGUGAAAAUGUCGUUGAUUAUUAUACCUAUGUACCUGAGUACUCUUGAUGUUUUCUGUGUUUAUAUUGUCUUUUUAUAGUUUUGUGUCAGUGUAAGAAAGGCCUUAUUUUGAAUUGAGAAGUGUUCUGCCCAGUUUCUGAAGACAUUGUGUAAACUUGAUGUUAAUUCCUAAAAUACUUGGCCGAAUUAUCUAGUGAUGCCAUACUAUUCUGGGUCUUCUUUUUUGGACUUUUAAAGUAAAAAUUCAUUGUCUUUAGUUGUCACAGACUAUUCAGAUUUUCUCUUAUAUCUUGAUUGACUUGCCAGAUUGUGAGUUUUGAAGAAUUGUUUCUUUUAAGUUACAGAAUUCCCCAUGGUAUUUUUAUUAUAAUUUCAGUAGUAUAGUAUCUGCAGUAAUGUAUUUUAUUCCUUAUUGAUAUUUUGUGAUUUCACUCACAAGUUUUUUUAAAGCAAAAUUUUCUUUUAUUUAUUCUACUGUUUUUCCCCACAUUUCAUCGAUUUUUCUUCCCCCUCUCACCCACAGCCCCUUUUGAGUUUGUUUUGCUCUUCAUUCUUUAGUUACUUUUUAUAGUUACUUCAGUUAAUUUAAACUGUUUUCAACCAGGCACAAUACCUCAUGCCUGUAAACCCAGUACUUUGUGAGUCCAAGGCAGCAGGAUUGCUUGAGCCCAGGAGUUCAGGACUGGCCUGGACAAUAUAAUGAGACCUCAACUCUAUAAAAAACUAAAACAUUAGACAGGCAUGAUGUUGUAUGCCUAUAGUUGCAGCUUCUCAGGAAAUUGAGGCAGUAGGCUUCCUUGAGCCUGCAGUGAGCUGUGAUUGUGCCACUGCCCUCCAGCCUAGGCAACAGAGUGGGACCUUGUCUCAAAUAAUAAUAAUUCUCUCUUUCUAUACACGCAUUUAGUGAAAUAACUCCCUUUUCACAGCUAAUAGCCUGCAUAUUUUGAUAUGUUGUAUUUUAAUUUUUAUUCAGUUUUAUGUAUUUUAAAAAUUUCCUUUAGGAUUUUCUCUUAGAUCAAUGUAUUUAGAACUGUUUAAUUCCCAAGUGGUGGGGAGUGGGGAGGCUUUAUUUUUGUAUAAUACCGAUUUCCACUUUGGUUUGACUUUGCUCAGAAAAUACACUGUGUAUUAUUUCAGUUCUUUUAAAUUUGUUGAUGUUUGACUUAUGUCUUAAUGUUGAUGUUUGAGUUACUUACUGCCUGAGCUGCACACUCCACAGGGCCACUGGGAGCUGAGGACAAGUGGGGGCGCCGCCCUCCCACUUCCAAGUUGAUGGGGUGGGAGUUUCCCAGUGCAGCUGCAGCCACCCAAGUCAUGGCUGUGGACCUGGGCCUCCCUGUGCUCUUGAGCCUUCCCACAGCUGCAGAGCCAGACAUCUCUGCACUCUCAGGGGCCCAGGAAGGAUCCCUCCCCCACAGGCUUGGAGGUGUCUGCUCCUGCUGCCUGGCCUCUCCCAGCUCCCAAGUGCCUAUUCUGAUCUCAGAGCAAGGUUGGGGCCAAGACUUGGCAUUGUGUCAGCCCGGCCAGCUGUGCUCAUGCUCAAGGCAGCACUGACAUGCCAGCCUUCCACCUUCUUGGCCCACUCUGAACUUUGGGCACUGAUGAGCAUAAGAGGGAAGCUGAUGGGGGGCUGAGGGCAGCUUGCACUGACCUGCAGGUGUUCCUUGAUAUAUACAUCCUGGGUGCCAUGAAAGGCAGCAGGAGGCAGACAUGUUCCUGAGUGCAAGGGGGUGGGCCCCUGGUGAGGCCCCACCUUCAGGCCAGGGAGGACCUGAAGGGUGGGAACUGGCCUGCCAGUCCUGCAAACCCCAAUGUGAACUUGUGGUGCCUUUUCCAGGCCUCCCCAUGGCCACCCAUGGACCAGUCGGCAUUCACUUCCUCCCUUCUGCGGCCCAUAAAAGCCCUGGGUUCAGGCAGAGCUGAGCAGACAUCAGGUGACCAGCUGCAGAAAGGAGCUACCCACUCCAGGGCCUCAUCUCUGCUGAGAGCUGCAGAGAUGACCAGAAGACCUGCAUCCAGAGAGGAGCUUCCUGAUCCAGGGCUAUUCUGUCACUCAAUAAAGCUUCUCUUUGUCUUGUUCUCCUUCCA